GCUUCCUAGGAACAGAUCGUGUAGAAGAGAAAACUUCAGUGAUAACCAUCAGAGUUAGUGUGACCCAGUGAGGGCUGGUGGGGUAAGAAGGAAAAGAGGAGAGAGAAUAAGUACUAGCCUUCACAGUAAUGAGCCUGGAAAGUCCCAUACUUAUUGAGUCUAUGAAGGUGAAGUCCCUGUACUUUGAUGGUACUUUAGUUUUCACAGAAACCAGUGUCUCCCACCUUCUGUUCUCACUCCUUGGAAUCCAGGGCCCGUCUUUAAUAAGUUAUUUUCCGAACAGUCUCUAACUCUCCUGCACUCUUUCCUAUAAACUUUAGUCUCCUGUUGAAUUUCGUACAUCCAGUUACUUAUUCAUUAACUACUCACGGAAGAUCUACUAUGCUCAAGACACAACAGCUACAUGGAAGCAGAAAACCUUACAGAAUUAUCAAAAUUUCUCCUCCUGGGACUCUCAGAUGAUCCUGAACUGCAGCCCGUCCUCUUUGGGCUGUUCCUGUCCAUGUACCUGGUCACGGUGCUGGGGAACCUGCUCAUCAUUCUGGCCGUCAGCUCUGACUCCCACCUCCACACCCCCAUGUACUUCUUCCUCUCCAACCUGUCCUUUGUUGACAUCUGUUUCAUCUCCACCACAGUCCCCAAGAUGCUAGUGAGCAUCCAGGCACGGAGCAAAGACAUCUCCUACAUGGGGUGCCUCACUCAGGUGUAUUUUUUAAUGAUGUUUGCUGGAAUGGAUACUUUCCUACUGGCCGUGAUGGCCUAUGACCGGUUUGUGGCCAUCUGCCACCCACUGCACUACACGGUCAUCAUGAACCCCUGCCUCUGUGGCCUCCUGGUUCUGGCAUCUUGGUUCAUCAUUUUCUGGUUCUCCCUGGUUCAUAUUCUACUGAUGAAGAGGUUGACCUUCUCCACAGGCACUGAGAUUCCGCAUUUCUUCUGUGAACCGGCUCAGGUCCUCAAGGUGGCCUGCUCUAACACCCUCCUCAAUAACAUUGUCUUGUAUGUGGCCACGGCACUGCUGGGUGUGUUUCCUGUAGCUGGGAUCCUCUUCUCCUACUCUCAGAUUGUCUCCUCCUUAAUGGGAAUGUCCUCCACCAAGGGCAAGUACAAAGCCUUUUCCACCUGUGGAUCUCACCUCUGUGUGGUCUCCUUGUUCUAUGGAACAGGACUUGGGGUCUAUCUGAGUUCUGCUGUGACCCAUUCUUCCCAGAGCAGCUCCACCGCCUCAGUGAUGUACGCCAUGGUCACCCCCAUGCUGAACCCCUUCAUCUACAGCCUGAGGAACAAGGAUGUGAAGGGGGCCCUGGAAAGACUCCUCAGCAGGGCCGACUCUUGUCCAUGACAAAUCAGGGCCUCAGAACUAAGAGGACACACUGCGUACCCCUAAGGCAAAUGUUGUGGGUUUAAAUAUCCGGCUCUUUUUCUCUUUUAAAAAAUGUGCUUGAUGUGGGAUUUUUGGUUGUUGUUAUUGGGUUGUUUGUUGUUGUUAUUGUUAUUGUUUUUGAGACAGAGUCUGGCUCUGUCGCCCAGGCUAGAGUGCAGUGGUGCAAUCUUGGCUCACUGCAACCUCUACCUCCCAGGUUGAAGCGGUUCUCCUGCCUCAGCCUCUCAAGUAGCUGAGAUUACAGGUGUGUGCCACCACAGCCAGCUAAUUUUUGUAUUUUUAGUAGAGACAGGGUUCCACCAUACUGUUCAGGCUGGUCUGGAACUCCUGACCUCAUGAUCUGCCUGCCUCAGCCUCCCAAAGUGCUAGGAUUACAAGCGUGAGCCACCGUGCCUGGCCAAUGUGUUUCUUUCUUUUCUUUUUUUUUUUAAUCAAAAACAACUAUGAUUUUGCUUUUGUUUUUGUGUUAGUUUCUCCUAAAAACUCCCUCUGUAAGCCCUUUUUGACUUUUCUUCCCUAGAUGUUUCCCAUAAAGUUCCAUCUUUGAUCAGUUUUCUUACCACUCUUUCUGAGACUUCUAAUUUGAUGUGUAUGGCACUCCCAAUAUCAAGUGCUGACCUGGUUUCCUCAAAAAUUAUCCUGUUGAAUGUUGAUGUUCCUCACCUUAGUAUAGUUUUUUCUUGUCCUCUGGAUAGGAAAUAAAAUGAAAACCAUAGAUUAGUCGUAUAAAAUGUUUACAAUAUCAGGACAGUGCUUGUUGCUUUACAUGUCUGAUGUUAUUCAAUCCUGAAAACAUUUCGUGAGAAAUUUUGUCUCAUUCACUGCAUUUCUCAAAGGAGGAGACUGAGAUGGAGGUAGAGUAUAUCCUAACAAUCUGACACUUUGCCCACACUUCUAACUUUGCCAUCCUACUUUCCAUAAAAACAGUGAUAUAAAAUUUUCGGGGCACAGUGGCUCACACCUGUCUUCCCAGCUACUUGGAGGGCUGAGGCAGGAGAAUCACUGGAGCCUAGGAGUUUGAGGCUGUAGUGAGCUGUGAUCGUGGCACUGCAAUCCAGCCUGGGUGACAGAGCAAGACCCUGUCUCAAACCAAAAACAAACACAAAAGCAAAGAAUGAUAAUGUGAUUUUCAACUUCAAAUUAUGACUCUAUAUUUGAAAGCUGGUUGGGUCAAAUGGUUCCUAGUAAUAUACUGGCCAGAAUGAGUCUGACAUGCUAUCCCUUUGAAAUACAAGCCCUAUAAGCCCACAGAAAUCAGAGCCGUGGAAUCUGGGAGCACAAACCCCUUAGGUGUCUCACUACAGGUGAUGUUAGGCAGGGCCAAUCUUGUUCCAACUCUUGAUUUCCGGGCCAUUGUAUUCUAUAUCAUAAAGAUAUUAUCAUUUUGAUGGUAUCAAAAGAUAUUAUCAUUUUUCACUGAUUUGGAAUGCAUACUAAUCCUAAUUUGCAUCCUGCAAAUUUGGUAGCCAGUAUUUUCUGUUUAUUCAAAUACCUGCAAUAAAUAUUUGUCUUUGAAAUAAAACUCAGGUGGCAGAGGUUGCAGUGAGCUGAGAUUGUGCCACUGCACUCCAGCCUGGGCGACAGAGCAAGACUCUGUCUAAAACAUAAAACAAAAUAAAUAAAUAAAACAAAAUAACUUAGAAAGUAUAAUUGCAUUGUUUGUAACUCUAAAGAUAAAUAGUUGAGGGAUGAAUACCUCAUUCUCCACGAUGUGGUUAUUUCACAUUGCAUUCCUGUAUCAAAACGUUUCAUCUACCCCAUAAAUAUAUACAGCUACUAUCUACGCACAAAAAUUAAAAAUGUUUUAAAACAUUUUUAAAGAAAAAUAAAAGUAGAAGAGGAGAAAAGUGAAUGACCAUUGAAGGAACAGGGCUUCCUCUUCUCAUUAAAACCUCUUCUGUCCUCUGAGUUCCCACCACCAAGUUUCAGAGACAGUGACAAACCACAUCAGAUUUUUUUUUAAUUUUAAAAUGAAAUGGGAGUCAUAUCUGCAAAUCCAUUGAAUGAACCAUGUAAAUAAAGAAGAAGCAGGCCUUCCAUGAGAAGAAUAUGUUGCACCUUUUUUUUUUUUUUUUUUUUUUUGAGAUGGAGUCUUGCUCUGUCGCCCAGGCUAGAGCACAGUGGCGCUGGGAUUACAGGCGCACGCCACCAUGCCCGGCUAAUCUUUUGUAUUUUUAGUAGAGAUGGGGUUUCACCAUGCUGGCCAGGCUGGUCUCAAACUCCUGACCUCGUGAUCCACCCGCCUCGGCCUCCCAAAGUGCUGGGAUUACAGGCAUGACCCACCACACCCAGCCACUACUUUCAUUCUUGAAGUUCAGAUUUAUGUUUCUAAGGAGGACUUUCUAUUUUACUUUCUAUACUCCUUGCCUGUAAUUUGAGAUUUUAUGCAUUGGUAAUUUAUGUUUUUGCUAAGUUGGAUAAGACCCUAAUUCUUUCUGUCUGAUUGAUCUAUGUUGGCAUGUUAGAAACUGCUGAUCUUUGCAGCCUAACUUGGUAACUUUAUAUAUUGCUUAAGCAUUUCCCCAUAUCUAACAAGACUGCAAUCAGAUGUCAGCCAGGGUUGCAGUCAUCUCGUGGACUGACUGGAGAGGAUCUGCUGUGAAGCUCACUCACAUGGCUGUUUGUAGGGUUUAGGUUCUUGCAGGACAAUGGCCUAAGGCCCCUCAGUUUGUUGCCACAAGGGACUCUCAUGGGGCAGCUCACAUAUGCCAGCUGAGUUCUGUCAGUGCAGGGAAGCAAGGGACAGAGCAACAGAGGCCAGGCCUAUCCUUCUACCAGGACAUGGGUCUCUAAGCACCCAAGACCAUGGAGAUUUCCCUCUGCCUUCCGGUAGAGUUCCUCACCAUUCAAGACAUUGUACUGUCAGAAAAAUUCCAUGCUGUAGAACUGGCACAUGGACAUGUCGCCCUUUCCUCUGCACUGGAUAUUUCUACAGACUUAACAAUGUUCUCCUGGACCUUCAGACAAAAUAAGCCACCCUGGUUCUCCUUCGCCACAAGCUCUCAGCCCAACAUCACAAUAAGCUGCUGCAAUUCUGCACCUAAAUUCAGCAAGUGUUCCCAGCAGCUUCUGAUUGUUGCUCAUCAAGAAAGAGCUCAUCUCACUUCAGGCGGAGAACUCCCUAGUGUAGACUCUGUGUUGUGUGUGUUGUGUGUGUGUGUGUGUGUGUGAGAUCACCUAGUAAAUUCUUUAAUGAAAUGUACUUUCUUUUGGCCUGUCUUUAUUCAAGUAGAUAAAAUAGGUUGUAUGGAAGUUAUGGAGUUUUUGUUUUGUUUUGUUUUGAGAUGUCUUGCUCUGUUGCCCAAGCUGCAGUGAAGCGGCUCAGUCAUAGCUCACUGCAGCCUUGAAUUCCUGGCCUCAAGUAAUCCUCCUGCGCCACCAUGUCCAGGUAAUUUAUUUUAUUUUAUUUUUUUGUAGAGAUGGAGUCUUGCUAUGUUGCCCAGGCUGGUCUUGAACUUCUGGUCUCAAGUGACCCUCCUGCUUCAGCCUCCCAAAGUGGUGAGAUUGUAGGUACAGACCACCAUGCCCAGCCAGAUAUUAUGGUUCUUUAUAAACUUUCACAUUCCACCCAUGGCUCAGAG